UCACUGACCCCACUCCUGAGCAUGAACUCUCCUCCCCUCCACUCUGCUGUCAGGUUUUGUCUCCAUUGGCCAAGAACCUCUUCCACCGGGCCAUUUCUGAGAGUGGCGUGGCCCUCACUUCUGUUCUGGUGAAGAAAGGUGAUGUCAAGCCCUUGGCUGAGCAAAUUGCUAUCACUGCUGGGUGCAAAACCACCACCUCUGCUGUCAUGGUUCACUGCCUGCGACAGAAGACGGAAGAGGAGCUCUUGGAGACGACAUUGAAAAUGAAAUUCUUAUCUCUGGACUUACAGGGAGACCCCAGAGAGAGUCAACCCCUUCUGGGCACUGUGAUUGAUGGGAUGCUGCUGCUGAAAACACCUGAAGAGCUUCAAGCUGAAAGGAAUUUCCACACUGUCCCCUACAUGGUCGGAAUUAACAAGCAGGAGUUUGGCUGGUUGAUUCCAAUGCAGUUGAUGAGCUAUCCACUCUCCGAAGGGCAACUGGACCAGAAGACAGCCAUGUCACUCCUGUGGAAGUCCUAUCCCCUUGUUUGCAUUGCUAAGGAACUGAUUCCAGAAGCCACUGAGAAAUACUUAGGAGGAACAGACGACACUGUCAAAAAGAAAGACCUGUUCCUGGACUUGAUAGCAGAUGUGAUGUUUGGUGUCCCAUCUGUGAUUGUGGCCCGGAACCACAGAGAUGCUGGAGCACCCACCUACAUGUAUGAGUUUCAGUACCGUCCAAGCUUCUCAUCAGACAUGAAACCCAAGACGGUGAUAGGAGACCACGGGGAUGAGCUCUUCUCCGUCUUUGGGGCCCCAUUUUUAAAAGAGGGUGCCUCAGAAGAGGAGAUCAGACUUAGCAAGAUGGUGAUGAAAUUCUGGGCCAACUUUGCUCGCAAUGGAAACCCCAAUGGGGAAGGGCUGCCCCACUGGCCAGAGUACAACCAGAAGGAAGGGUAUCUGCAGAUUGGUGCCAACACCCAGGCGGCCCAGAAGCUGAAGGACAAAGAAGUAGCUUUCUGGACCAACCUCUUUGCCAAGAAGGCAGUGGAGAAGCCACCCCAGACAGAACACAUAGAGCUGUGAAUGAAGAUCCAGCCGGCCUUGGGAGCCUGGAGGAGCAAAGACUGGGGUCUUUUGCGAAAGGGAUUGCAGGUUCAGAAGGCAUCUUACCAUGGCUGGGGAAUUGUCUGGUGGUGGGGGGCAGGGGACAGAGGCCAUGAAGGAGCAAGUUUUGUAUUUGUGACCUCAGCUUUGGGAAUAAAGGAUCUUUUGAAGGCCAAA